AGAUUCCAGCGAGCUACGCAAGCAAUCCUGGCCCAGCCGAGCUUGCUUCCCCAAAUCCCGUAAUCCUUGACCUUAUUCCCCCAAAGAAGCGGCCUCCCGGGAAGGAGCGCCCUGGCGGAGAAGACUCGAACGGCUCCCACAGCCGGGCGUUGGGGGAAAGCUCAGGCAUGAAGAACUCUUGACUGACAGAAACGGAGGGUGUGUCCAAAGUUUUGAGGACGGCCGAGCGGCGCUCCAAAACCCGUCCUCACAGCCUCGCCCCGUUCGCCUCAGCUACAACAAAUCAUCGUCAACCUGUUCCACCUUCUCCAGUCUGGUAGCAAAAAGGGGUGUCUCAGAAUCUCCGGCCUGUGAAACUGUGAGGGGAUUCGGCCAAGACGUCCUCUUCCCUCUGCCUCCCACCCAGGCCACUCUUCACCUCCACCAUGAGCCUGGACAUCCAGAGCCUGGACAUCCAGUGUGAGGAGCUGAGCGACGCUAGAUGGGCCGAGCUCCUCCCUCUGCUCCAGCAGUGCCAAGUGGUCAGGCUGGACGACUGUGGCCUCACGGAAGCACGGUGCAAGGACAUCAGCUCUGCACUUCGAGUCAACCCUGCACUGGCAGAGCUCAACCUGCGCAGCAACGAGCUGGGCGAUGUCGGCGUGCAUUGCGUGCUCCAGGGCCUGCAGACCCCCUCCUGCAAGAUCCAGAAGCUGAGCCUCCAGAACUGCUGCCUGACGGGGGCCGGCUGCGGGGUCCUGUCCAGCACACUACGCACCCUGCCCACCCUGCAGGAGCUGCACCUCAGCGACAACCUCUUGGGGGAUGCGGGCCUGCAGCUGCUCUGCGAAGGACUCCUGGACCCCCAGUGCCGCCUGGAAAAGCUGCAGCUGGAGUAUUGCAGCCUCUCGGCUGCCAGCUGCGAGCCCCUGGCCUCCGUGCUCAGGGCCAAGCCGGACUUCAAGGAGCUCACGGUUAGCAACAACGACAUCAAUGAGGCUGGCGUCCGUGUGCUGUGCCAGGGCCUGAAGGACUCCCCCUGCCAGCUGGAGGCGCUCAAGCUGGAGAGCUGCGGUGUGACAUCAGACAACUGCCGGGACCUGUGCGGCAUUGUGGCCUCCAAGGCCUCGCUGCGGGAGCUGGCCCUGGGCAGCAACAAGCUGGGUGAUGUGGGCAUGGCGGAGCUGUGCCCAGGGCUGCUCCACCCCAGCUCCAGGCUCAGGACCCUGUGGAUCUGGGAGUGUGGCAUCACUGCCAAGGGCUGCGGGGAUCUGUGCCGUGUCCUCAGGGCCAAGGAGAGCCUGAAGGAGCUCAGCCUGGCCGGCAACGAGCUGGGGGAUGAGGGUGCCCGACUGCUGUGUGAGACCCUGCUGGAACCUGGCUGCCAGCUGGAGUCGCUGUGGGUGAAGUCCUGCAGCUUCACAGCCGCCUGCUGCUCCCACUUCAGCUCAGUGCUGGCCCAGAACAGGUUUCUCCUGGAGCUACAGAUAAGCAACAACAGGCUGGAGGAUGCGGGCGUGCGGGAGCUGUGCCAGGGCCUGGGCCAGCCUGGCUCUGUGCUGCGGGUGCUCUGGUUGGCCGACUGCGAUGUGAGUGACAGCAGCUGCAGCAGCCUCGCCGCAACCCUGUUGGCCAACCACAGCCUGCGUGAGCUGGACCUCAGCAACAACUGCCUGGGGGACGCCGGCAUCCUGCAGCUGGUGGAGAGCGUCCGGCAGCCGGGCUGCCUCCUGGAGCAGCUGGUCCUGUACGACAUUUACUGGUCUGAGGAGAUGGAGGACCGGCUGCAGGCCCUGGAGAAGGACAAGCCAUCCCUGAGGGUCAUCUCCUGAGGCUCUUCCUGCUGCUGCUCUCCCUGGACGACCGGCCUCGAGGCAACCCUGGGGCCCACCAGCCCCUGCCAUGCUCUCACCCUGCAUAUCCUAGGUUUGAAGAGAAACGCUCAGAUCCGCUUAUUUCUGCCAGUAUAUUUUGGACACUUUAUAAUCAUUAAAGCACUUUCUUGGCA